GCACAAGUACACAAAGACACAGAAGCGCACGGACGUGCACACGCGCCUAAACAACUACGGGGACGCCCGUUGCCCAUACUCAGGCCUUGUGGUGCUGGACGUGUGAAUGUUAGCAGUGAGCCGGGAAAAGUUAGCGAAGGCUGGGCUGUGCGGCUUCUCCUGUGCGUGCAUCUGACUCCCGUAUAGUGUGCACUUAAGGCGGGCCUGAGAGCGUGGGGCUCUGCAGGGAUCUCCUAGAUAUCCCCGCGCCCCUCCUCAGCCCCAAUGGAAUAAUCUGAGGGGGUCGCUCUCAGAAACCCAGGCCUCCAUGCUAGCCUGGAAAGUUUGGGAAACAGGAAUGGGAGGGUUAUGCUGCACGCCACCACUUAGGUGCGCGUGUUGAUUAGACGCGUCGGCUUUUGUCAGCGCGUAGGUCAGGCAGGGAUUCCUCCACUUGUCCUCUGUUUGCUGAGGAUGAGGCCCUGCCUGGGAAUUUUGUGUGACAAAGACGAUACCCUUCCUGGGGCCGUCUAUUAGGGACCUCGCCCGAGAGUCUAGUGGAAGAUGAGUAAGAGGUCGGGAGCCUACGACGUGACUUCCUGCGGCGGAGCUGGAAGGAGGAGCGCCUUGAAGGAGCUUAGCCCCCGCCUCUGCAACCCACCACCGUCUCCCCCUUUGGUUUCUCCUAGCCCCAUCUGGUUCGCAUUGCACUCCCGCCCACGGCUGGGAGGGCUGUUGGGGGAGGCGGGGGCUCUAAGGGCCCGGCCCAUAGACUCUAAGCCCCAGGGAAAGGAGGGGGGGUGGGGGCCGGGGAAAGCGAGCGGACUGGCCACAGCUGAAACUGAUGUAAAUGUGGUCAUGCUUCAGGAAUCCCAAGUUUGUGAAAAGCGUGCCAGCCAACAAUUCUGUUACACAAAUGUGCUUAUCCCAAAAUGGCAUGAUAUAUGGACACGGAUACAGAUCCGAGUAAAUAGUUCCAGAUUGGUUCGAGUCACCCAGGUGGAGAAUGAGGAGAAACUGAAGGAGCUAGAGCAGUUUAGUAUCUGGAACUUUUUUUCCUCCUUUUUAAAAGAGAAAUUGAAUGACACCUAUGUUAACGUGGGUCUAUACAGCACAAAAACCUGCCUCAAAGUUGAGAUUAUAGAGAAGGACACCAAGUACAGUGUCAUUGUGAUCCGGAGAUUUGAUCCCAAACUCUUUCUUGUUUUCCUUCUUGGACUUAUGCUAUUUUUUUGUGGAGACUUGCUGAGCAGAAGUCAAAUUUUCUACUACUCUACUGGGAUGACUGUGGGAAUUGUGGCCUCUCUGCUAAUCAUCAUUUUUAUACUAUCUAAGUUUAUGCCUAAGAAAAGUCCCAUUUACGUCAUCCUGGUGGGAGGCUGGUCUUUUUCUCUGUACCUCAUUCAACUAGUUUUUAAAAAUUUACAAGAGAUCUGGAGGUGUUACUGGCAGUAUCUUUUAAGUUAUGUCCUCACAGUUGGAUUCAUGAGUUUUGCAGUAUGUUACAAGUAUGGGCCCUUGGAGAAUGAACGAAGUAUCAACCUGCUGACCUGGACCUUGCAGCUGAUGGGCCUGUGUUUCAUGUAUUCUGGCAUCCAGAUACCACAUAUUGCCCUUGCCAUUAUCAUCAUUGCUCUUUGUACUAAGAACCUGGAACACCCUAUUCAGUGGCUGUACAUCACCUGCAGAAAGGUGUGUAAGGGAGCAGAAAAGCCUGUUCCCCCUCGUCUCCUGACAGAAGAAGAAUAUCGGAUACAAGGAGAGGUAGAAACCCGAAAGGCUUUAGAGGAGCUCCGAGAAUUUUGUAACAGUCCAGACUGCUCUGCUUGGAAGACUGUUUCUCGAAUCCAGUCUCCAAAAAGAUUUGCUGACUUUGUGGAAGGCUCUUCCCACCUCACGCCAAAUGAAGUUUCUGUCCAUGAGCAGGAGUAUGGAUUAGGGAGCAUUAUUGCCCAGGAUGAAAUCUAUGAGGAAGCAUCCUCUGAGGAGGAGGACUCAUAUUCUCGGUGUCCUGCUAUCACACAGAACAACUUUCUAACCUAGGUAGUGGUCAGUUAUCUUUACGUGGACUGGCUUGGUGCCUUGGUCCAUGUUGCAUGUGUUGUGCAAUUGCUUUCAACCCUUUGAAACAGAGUGAGAUAGAUAGGGUAGAAAUUCUCCUACUGAAAUAAGAGGCCUAAAAAGGCCUCCCUUUGGAAAUGGGAGGUCUCUAUGGGAUCCCUGAGGAAGGAGAGUGGAUAAAGUAGUGAAUGCUGGGUAGUUCACUUCCCAUUGGUUAAGCUAACAGCCCACUUUUAUGUUUCCAGAGAAAUUGGAUGGCCACAGCUAGCAUGGCAUUCUAGCUCCUUCUUGAAAGUUGAUUCAAUCAUGGCAUUUCUGUCACUGGCUGGCUCUCCAAAGUAAGAACUGUUGUUAAGUGCAGGAAUGCUUUUAGACUAUAGGCUGCAACUUCCAGAGAGAAAUCCACAAAUCUGAGCCUCCUUCACUCCAGCUUUUAUUUCAGUGACUUUAGAAUAAUUAUUGAUUUAACUGUUUUGGGAGGAAAAUAGAUUUUUAUUGUUUUGUUUUUUAAAUGAAUGUCUUUUAAAAAACAUAACAAACUCAUGUUCCAGAACCAGCAAGUGCUCCAGAGUGACACACCCCCUAGGCCCCUACAUAUUUAUUAAUAUGGAUUAUCCAUUAAAGCCCCAGGAGCUGUUGUUUUAAGCUUUGAUUUAGUUCUCAUACAUAUGAUAGAAAGUCCUAUUUGCCUUUAGGAACAUGCCUGUAGGCUCUUCUGCAGGUGAGAUGUACUGGGCUUUUUAUUAUAUUCAACUUUCAAUUCCAUCUUAAAAAACAUUUGUAUUCUUCUCUUCCCAUUCUUCCUUACCCUGCCUUUGCCCUUUCAGGAAGGGUCAGUUCCCUUACCUGUGAACUAUGUAUGUUCAGAGUAGCAUUAUUCCUGCUAGCUAGGAGAAGUCAUCUUGUUUAGGGGAUUUGGAUGCUUUUUAUACGUUCUCCAUUUUCCUGUCAUUGGGUCAUGUUAUCUUUGAGUUGCUAUGAAAUCAGGAAACUGUCUCCUUUUCCUUUCCCUUCCUUUGUCUACAUGCUCUGUCCAUUCCUUUCAGCCUUUUCUCACCACCCAUACUCCCCCAAAUCUGGGUAAUUUUUAAGCCUUGAAACUAUGUAGUUUCUUGAUACACAAUUUGUAGUUAUGCAGCAGCCACAAUUUGCAUUGCCAGGAAAUAGGCUCCAGGUUAUCUUCAUGCCUCUGGGUGCUCAUUCAGCUGUCAAGUUUCCAUGAACUUACACUUAUUUAUGAUUGCGUUUCUGACCUGAGAUGUAUGCUGCCUGUUAUUGCAGUAGCAUUAGUUUCAGAUUCUUUUGCCAUUGCAAAGUACCCCUUAUAAACCAGCAAUGUCAUCUGUGAGGAAGCAAAUUCUCAAGUGUCUGUCAUUUACUUGGUUCUUUUUCUUUGUGGUCUUCACCCUUAUACCCUGGAAAAGUCUGUAAUUACCUUAGCCAGGAAGAUAGAUGGUCAUGGCAAGCGCACAGCACCAGACUUACUGGCUCACCAAGAUGAUGGAAAAAGGCAGAUGAUUUUUUAAAAAGCCGUAAUGACUCCUUUAGACCAGCCAUUUAGCGUGGUAAUUUUGAAAGGCCUAGCUCCAUUGCAGACUUCCAAAGGGUCAGCUCUGAGACUGCCCUCCAGGUGGGCAGUUGAUUAUUUCCACCAGUGUUUUCCAGAGCCUUAAACUGUCCUAAGUGACAACUACCUCAGUUGGCAGGAAAGAGACAUAUAGUAGAAAGUGAAAAAUGAGCAGUAUUUGGGCAGAUGCUAUGGGUUACAGUUGAAGGGUAAAAGGAACUUUACAUUGGGAAACCUUUAUACCCUUGUGAAUUAUGUACAUGGUAAAAUGUUCUCUCUCUACAAAGAACUAUUAAAACUUCUGAAAUAUACUAUUUUUUACCUUAUUUAUAGAAAUUGAGACCUAGCAUAUUUAAGCAUAAGUUUAUUUUAAAAAAUAAUUCAACUCGUGCAAGUGGUCUCAGGAUUCUCUGGAGAUUUUGGUGCCUCCCCUACUUAGGGAGGUGAUAGCUUGCCUAUAAGGGUGACUUUUCCUGAUCAUGUCUUUAUUUCAAUGAGAAAGCACUGUGAAAUUGUGAAAGAUUCUCCUCUUUCUCUGUUUAAUAAACCCCCAUGAAAUAUAGUUUCCAUCUCUAGACCAGUUUUUUUUCCACCGUGUUUAGACUUGAGGUGAAUAAAAUCAAACUGUUUUUUACUCCCUAUCUGGUAGUUGGAGACCUGAGCUGUAGGCAGUGGAGAUGGCAAUUGGUUCUGCAGCCUGAGAGUUGCUCUCACACAGUGAAGGACGGUGCUGCUCUGGUGUGCUGUGUGUCCUUGCCCUGCCUGCCUGUGGCUCUGCCCAGAUGCUUCAGAUCCUCUGUGUUCCGGAGAUUGCUUGACUUCAACCUUCUUUAGGAGCUGCUCUUGUCUCCCUCUUGGCCACUUAGUUUGCUGGCUCAGUCACUACUUGAAGACCCCAUUUAAUUUUUCUCUGGCAGUUAUAGCUCUUGUGAUUUCAGUACAGUCUCAUCUCUCAGACCAAUCUCAUCAAGAAGGAUUGAAGGGAUAACUAUGAGGUAAGCUGGACAUUGGAGCCGUGUUUGCUGCCACGUCAGCGUCUUGCUGGGUGAAUGUCAAGCCAUAAAUGGGCUCCAGGGCUCUGGAUCUCAUCAGCAUUGGAAAUCUAUUGCCUCUCAUCAGUCUGACCAAAUUAUGUAGAGCAUUAAUGUAGAGACUCCCAUUAAUGGGAAUACAAGAGGCAGCUGGCAUAAAACAUUUCUUUCACUUUCCUUUCCCACUCAGAUUGCUUCAAGAGACCAACAGAACACAGGGAUCAAAAACAAGGAAAAUUUAGCAACUUCAUUACCUUCUAAUAAGUAAUUCCUGUUAGCCACUGCAUCCCACCAAAACUAGUUUAUUUUUCCCCUCAAAUUCAUGAUUUUUACGUCUGUUACAAAGGGAAUUUUGCUGAUAGCUCUUUGGGUCCCACUGUUCCAUUUUAUGCUAAUAGAUUCCAUUCUAGGGCCCAGCCGUCUCUUGACUGAUGGUGUUCCCUUUAACCCUUGGCAUGUAUAAUAGAAUUUUGGUGAAUGAAAGAACCCAAAUAGGCCAGAUAGUCCCCCCAGGCCCUGAUAUCCAUAAAAGGCUUGGGAAUGCAUUAUGUAAUUGUCCUUAGUCUUUUUGUUGUUUUAGAAAAAAAAAACAAGAUGGGCUCAGAUGGAUGCCUACGUAAAAAUGGUUCCUAGCUGUGUACUCAUAACUUUUCUUUGAAUUGAGUAGUGAAAGGAAGGAGGAGGAAAGGAAAUUAAAUGUCCUUCUAGUAUUCUCUGGACUCAAGUCUGACAUAUGAGAUAAUAACCUAUAUUGAAAUGCCAAGAAUUGUAUCUGAAACAAGAGAACAGUUUGACACAUUUAUCAUGCCUUCAUAUUACAUAUUAACUGAAACCAAUUAAUAAACAUAUGAAAUAUCCAUUGCACAAGGCAAAGGCACCUAAACCUUUUGUUUCUUUUUCUACAUAGCAGAAAUUGAUUUUUUUUUUAUUUUUUUAGGGGAACCUAUAUAAUUAUGACCCAGUGAUGUCUUUUGGUGACUUAAGCUUAUGAAUUCAGGUUACAAUUGAGUUGAUUCUAGAUGGUUACUACCUUGAAAAGGAUGUUGGUGCCUUAUGUGACACGAGCCAGAGCCUGCUGGGAAUAAACAAAGCAGAUUCAUGCCAACACCAACUCGUAGCUUUAGUGGCAGAUGGGAGUGGUCACAGACUCCCAAAAUGUGGGGCUUUGGAUUUCCACACCAUCCCACGUGUGUGUCAUCUUCCUCUUUCACACUCUUGAUGAUAAUUUGAAAAUGGUGAAAUCACCUCUGAAUUUGCCUAUAGCAUGAGCACAUUCUUAUGACAACAUAACAAAUAGUUCAUAAUGUGAAUAUUAGAAACUGUUACAGCCUGCAGUUACCAUAAUUUUCCAUGUUUGUGGAAUUGAUAUUGAAAUAGCAGGGCUAAGGAAUUACUGGCAAGUUUUAGCCUGUGGGUAAUACCUUAGGGUUAUUUAAAUAUUUGUAAUUUUAUUUAAAUGUUCAUGAAUGUUUGAAAGGAACAAAAUUAUCAGGGAUGGCUCUUUGCCAUGGGUCUUAUUUUCACCCUCUUUUCUGUAAGAAAAAAGAACAAUGUCUUAAUGUAUUUUUAAAGUUUUUGGUAUAGUUUCUAAUUCCAAUUUUAAUAAAAGUUUUAUAGAUA